AUCUUGGCAAGAGGCGAAGCGGCAGCGGUUCCUGUCAAGGGGGCAGCAGGUCCAGAGCUGCUGGUGCUCCCGUUCCCCAGACCCUACCCCUAUCCCCAGUGGAGCCGGAGUGCGGGCGCGCCCCACCACCGCCCUCACCAUGGUGCUGUUGGCAGCAGCGGUCUGCACAAAAGCAGGAAAGGCUAUUGUUUCUCGACAGUUUGUGGAAAUGACCCGAACUCGGAUUGAGGGCUUAUUAGCAGCUUUUCCAAAGCUCAUGAACACUGGAAAACAACAUACGUUUGUUGAAACAGAGAGUGUAAGAUAUGUCUACCAGCCUAUGGAGAAACUGUAUAUGGUACUGAUCACUACCAAAAACAGCAACAUUUUAGAAGAUUUGGAGACCCUAAGGCUCUUCUCAAGAGUGAUCCCUGAAUAUUGCCGAGCCUUAGAAGAGAAUGAAAUAUCUGAGCACUGUUUUGAUUUGAUUUUUGCUUUUGAUGAAAUUGUCGCACUGGGAUACCGGGAGAAUGUUAACUUGGCACAGAUCAGAACCUUCACAGAAAUGGAUUCUCAUGAGGAGAAGGUGUUCAGAGCCGUCAGAGAGACUCAAGAACGUGAAGCUAAGGCUGAGAUGCGUCGUAAAGCAAAGGAAUUACAACAGGCCCGAAGAGAUGCAGAGAGACAGGGCAAAAAAGCACCAGGAUUUGGCGGAUUUGGCAGCUCUGCAGUAUCUGGAGGCAGCACAGCUGCCAUGAUCACAGAGACCAUCAUUGAAACUGAUAAACCAAAAGUGGCACCUGCACCAGCCAGGCCUUCAGGCCCCAGCAAGGCUUUAAAACUUGGAGCCAAAGGAAAGGAAGUAGAUAACUUUGUGGACAAAUUAAAAUCUGAAGGUGAAACCAUCAUGUCCUCUAGUAUGGGCAAGCGUACUUCUGAAGCAACCAAAAUGCAUGCUCCACCCAUUAAUAUGGAAAGUGUACAUAUGAAGAUUGAAGAAAAGAUAACAUUAACCUGUGGACGAGACGGAGGAUUACAGAAUAUGGAGUUGCAUGGCAUGAUCAUGCUUAGGAUCUCAGAUGACAAGUAUGGCCGAAUUCGUCUUCAUGUGGAAAAUGAAGAUAAGAAAGGGGUGCAGCUACAGACCCAUCCAAAUGUGGAUAAAAAACUUUUCACUGCAGAGUCUCUAAUUGGCCUGAAGAAUCCAGAGAAGUCAUUUCCAGUCAACAGUGACGUAGGGGUGCUAAAGUGGAGACUACAAACCACAGAGGAAUCUUUUAUUCCACUGACAAUUAAUUGCUGGCCCUCGGAGAGUGGAAAUGGCUGUGAUGUCAACAUAGAAUAUGAGCUACAAGAAGAUAAUUUAGAACUGAAUGAUGUGGUUAUCACCAUCCCACUCCCGUCUGGUGUCGGCGCGCCUGUUAUCGGUGAGAUCGAUGGGGAGUAUCGACAUGACAGUCGACGAAAUACCCUGGAGUGGUGCCUGCCUGUGAUUGAUGCCAAAAAUAAGAGUGGCAGCCUGGAGUUUAGCAUUGCUGGGCAGCCCAAUGACUUCUUCCCUGUUCAAGUUUCCUUUGUCUCCAAGAAAAAUUACUGUAACAUACAGGUUACCAAAGUGACCCAGGUAGAUGGAAACAGCCCCGUCAGGUUUUCCACAGAGACCACUUUCCUAGUGGAUAAGUAUGAAAUUCUGUAAUACCAAGAAGAGGGAGCUGAAAAGGAAAAUUUUCAGAUUAAUAAAGAAGACGCCAAUGAUGGCUGAAGAGUUUUUCCCAGAUUUACAAGCCACUGGAGACCCCUUUUUUCUGAUACAAUGCACGAUUCUCUGCGCGCAAGGACCCUCGACUCACCCCCAUGUUUCAGUGUCACAGAGACAUUCUUUGAUAAGGAAAUGGCACAAACAUAAAGGGAAAGGCUGCUAAUUUUCUUUGGCAGAUUGUAUUGGCCAGCAGGAAAGCAAGCUCUCCAGAGAAUGCCCCCAGUUAAAUACCUCCUCUACCUUUACCUAAGUUGCUCCUUUAUUUUUAUUUUAUUAUUAUUAUUAUUAUUAUUAUUAUUUUUUGAGAUGGAGUCUCACUUUGUAACCCAGGCUGGAAUGCAAUGGCAUGAUCUCAGCUCACUGCAACCUCCGCCUCCUGGGUUCAAGCAAGUCUCCUGCCUCAGCCUCCGAGUAGCUGGGACUACAGGUGCACGCCACCACGCCUGGCUAAUUUUUUGUAUUUUAGUAGAGACGGGGUUUCACCGUGUUGCCCAGGCUGGUCGCGAACUCCUGAGCUCAGGCAAUCCGCCCACCUCAGCCUCCCAAAGUGUUGGGAUUACAGGCAUGAGCCACCAUGCCCAGCUGCUCCUUUAUUUUAAUCCCUAAAUAUAAUCCCUAAAUAUAGUUAUAUUUCAUACUUAGUUUGUUUUUAAAAAGUUUUCUCUGUAGAAAAUUUUAAUCAUUCAUACCCUUUACCUUUAGGUUUUUCUUUCUAUACAUUCAGUCAGGCACUGGGAUCAUCUGUUUACAGGCAUUAUAUUUAUUUGGCACUCCUGGAACAAGUAUAUCUAACCCAUUCUUGAUUUUUGGACUAUUCAGGUGAACUAUUUGAGGGGUAUGGGGUCUAGAAGUUAAAAGAUACGCAUGUCUUCUGUUCUUUUCCCGUAUCAAUUCAUUCCUUCAUCUCUUUGCCAAGUUGUUUUCCUUUCAGGGCCUGUCCUUCCAGUUUAGAACAGUACCAUGAAUCCCACUUGUGUCAAUAUUAAAGAUAGCUGAGAAGCACCUUUCAAAUGGCACAGUCCCUCUUCAAGAUGUCUAAAAGAAUGGUUAUGUCUGUCCAGUUAGGGAUUUCACAUCCACAUGUAAUCAUGUCUGCUGCUGUUGCUACCCAAAUUUUCAUUUCUCCACAUUUUGGGUACUUAAGCUAAAACGUAAUGGCCACAGUCUGUAAUCCAUUCACAUUCCUCAGUUUCACCACCUCCCUCUUCCAGACUGCACUCUCUGUCAUCAGUCCCCUCCUUUCUAACAGAAAUGGGGUUAUGAUUUUGAAGGCUGUGGGUUCAGGGAGUCUUUGCCAAUCCUGUUGGCCCUAAACUAUCAAGGAGGCUCCAUUUCACCAUUUGAUUUUUUGCAUUUCAGGAGGCAACUGAUUGUUUCGAUAUGUACAUAUUACUCACGUAUACCCCAUUUCCUUCCAGUCAGCCCAACAUUUUCCACCAGUCUGUCCCCAUCUCUGAAAUCCUUCCUUCUCUUUCCCCCUAAGUCUUUUGAGUGUCAUCAUGUACUGGUGGUUUCUCGGUUCCAUCUCAUCCAUUUCCUUUUCAAUGGAGACUACAGCGUCAGCCAGCUCAGCCUUGGCUUUUAACUCAAUAUUCCAGUCCAUAGGGGUGGUUAAAAGUUGCUGCAAGGCUGCAGGCACUGGCAGUGGGAAGAGGCAGACGACUAGAUGACUUCUGCACUUUUAGCUGGUUGAAAAGUACCACUCCCACUCUGAACAUCUGGCCGUCCCUGCAAAGAGUGUACUGUGCUUGAAGCAGAGCACUCACACAUAAAUGGCUGUGUGUGGAAUUGCUUGCCAAAGAAGUUUCUAGCCUUUCCCUUUCCCCUAACUGCAUCAGGGAAGAAUUCUUAUCUCUAGCUUGGUUUCCACAUGAGGUUUUUCUGAGAAGGGCUUGGGACAAGAAGUCUGUCAUGUUAGUUAAGCAGGCAAGAAAUCCUACUAAUCCAGUUUUGUUUGAAAGUUGUUUGUCCGUAUGAUUUUUUAAAAGUCAAGUUUAAUUUCAAAAAACCUUUUUUUUCUGAGAUUACUUUUGGGGUAAUAUUUAAAAUGAGAGACAUUUUGUAACCCUGUAAAAUACAUAGGGAAUAUAACAUUCCAGUGUAUACAAAGAAGGCAAAUUCUUUAAUCAAAUAAAGCGCAUUAUAAAAUGAGAUGUUUAUUGGAUUAUUGACUCACUUUGGUGUCUGCUUGUUGAUUCAGGAUGCUGUAAUGGGACCUAACAUUAAAAAUUAAUGACAUGUUUUUUUUAAGAGAAA